AGGGCGUGUUCGCUGUUCAGUGCCGGUGUUGCAGGGAGUGAGGGCAGCUGGAGUGCGUUCUGCCGAAGCUUGUGGUUGCACGCCCAUCGUCUUAGGGGCUACCUUCCGUGACCAUGUCCAAGUCUCUGAAGAAGUUGGUGGAGGAGAGCCGGGAGAAGAACCAGCCCGAGGUGGACAUGAGUGACCGGGGCAUCUCCAACAUGCUGGAUGUCAACGGCCUCUUUACCUUAUCCCAUAUCACACAACUGGUCCUCAGCCAUAACAAGCUAACAAUGGUGCCACCGAACAUCGCAGAACUGAAGAAUUUGGAGGUGCUCAACUUUUUUAAUAACCAAAUCGAGGAGCUGCCCACACAGAUCAGUAGCCUUCAGAAACUCAAACACCUGAACCUUGGCAUGAACAGGCUGAACACUUUGCCACGAGGCUUCGGCUCCCUGCCAGCUCUUGAGGUUCUGGACUUGACGUACAACAACUUGAGCGAAAAUUCUCUUCCUGGAAACUUCUUCUACCUGACCACCCUGCGUGCACUCUAUCUAAGUGACAACGAUUUUGAAAUCCUGCCGCCAGAUAUUGGGAAGCUCACAAAGUUGCAGAUACUCAGCCUUAGGGAUAACGACCUGAUCUCGCUGCCUAAGGAAAUCGGGGAGCUUACCCAGCUUAAAGAGCUCCACAUUCAGGGGAACCGCCUCACCGUUCUGCCCCCAGAACUAGGAAACUUGGAUUUAACUGGCCAGAAGCAGGUAUUCAAAGCAGAGAACAAUCCCUGGGUGACCCCCAUUGCAGACCAGUUCCAGCUUGGCGUGUCCCAUGUUUUUGAGUAUAUCCGUUCUGAGACAUACAAAUACCUCUACGGCAGACACAUGCAGGCCAACCCAGAACCACCGAAGAAGAAUAAUGACAAAUCGAAAAAGAUCAGCCGGAAACCCCUGGCAGCCAAGAACAGAUAAGGAAGGGAUUGGCAUCGGCUGGCCUUCCAGCACCUUCUCUCUCCAACACUUCAUUCUCUCUUGCCCUGUCUCUCAAAUAAACCCAAUGCUGCGUGUGAGGCCUUUUUUAUUUUUCUUUUCACUCUCUUUCUAAUGCUUCCCACCUUACCUUUUAGAUUCUUUUGCUAGGUGGGAGAUUGUUAUAAGGUCUUUAAACCAUUUCCAUUUGUUUCUUUAACAUUACCAAAAGCAGGGAACAAAGCUCUUAUUCAACUGCGAAUUCCAUAGUGGGCUCUGGCUUUUCUUGAAUAGAUAUCACAAGGUUGCUUAUUAUCAAAAGAAUAAUUAAAAUCAUGUAACCAUUUAAAUGUCACUGUUAACACUUUUCACUCUUUCUGUUGAUUCACCUAACUCAUUAUUUUGCUUUAUUAAAAGUCUUCCUUCACCACCGAGAUAUGCUAAUUUAACUUACAAAUGAUUUUAAUAAAAUCUUGAGUUUGUAUCACAUGUUACUUAUUGACUCAGAAUAAAAGAACAGUCUGAUCUUGGGGUAUAACACAUUUUCAUUUACUUUUCUCCCCCAAAAUCAUCUUAUCCAAUUUUAUUGGUUAUACAUGAUAAACUUUUCAUGAAAGAAAUGCAAAAUUAAAUCACAGUUCGUUUCUUCUCACAUUAAUUUGUCAAGUUUUUUUUUUCUUUGAAGACUUUCUAAAUUAGGAAGCAGAAAAACAAAUCUCUAGGAGAUUCUGCCAAAGGAUUUUGGAAAGUAGCAUUCCUUCGCCGAAGAAAUGGUGAUUUCUGCCAGGGGCUGGUAGACAAGAACUGUGAAAGAGAGAGAGAAAAAACCUCAACUGUGUAUUUUGUCACGGCGGAAAAUCUGCUCGCAUCGAAGCAUUCUUCUAAGCGACUUCGAUGCCAAGGAAGUUGUGUAAAUGUGCACGCGCUACACCACACCCAGGGUGGAAACCACAGUUGCAGAGUCAUUAAACAAUCAAUUGUUUGUUUAACAUCUGUGAUAGGCAGCUUUCCUUCUUUUCAACAGUGAUACCUACGAAAAUCAAAAUAAAUGCAAGCUGAGGUUUUGUGCUCACUGAAAGGGCUGUCAACCCCAGAAGGCCGACACAAAAAAAAUGGUAUGUGAAGAUGCACCGUCUUUUCAAAUGGCCUGGGAGAGUCAAAUGGCCUGGGAGAGGGGGCCUGCCCUUCUCUGCUGUGUCCUUUCGGCUUCCCAGUUGAGCUCCCAAGACCAGGACCCACUGGGGCAUAUAAAAUCUCUGCUGUAUCCUUUCGGCUUCCCAGUUGAGCUCCCAAGACCAGGACCCACUGGGGCAUAUAAAAAAGUCAAAAAUCAAAAUCAAACAACAAGUUCUGAGUUACUUAGGAAACAGACUUCGCAUUUCAAUCAGAGAGGCCACAGAGCAAGGUCUAAACUUCUGGCUUCUAGACAAAUUCCUGAUAGAACAUUUAAAUGUGGGAAGUGGCUUCCCCAGGUCCCAUCCCCUGUUUAGGGAUAGAGUUGAUAUCAUUUUUAUAGGUGCCAUGUAUGCCUCUGCCUGAAUUUUUUUAAUUGACUUUUGAGCUUUUGAGAUUGCACGAGGGAGAACAAGGCCUUUGCUGUUGUGGAUAGGAAAGACUUAACCUAAAAUUAAACCAGCAAGAAAGCAUUAGUAAAAAUCUAACAAUAUGAAGGGCUCUUAUGAGUCAUUUUUUUCAAAAGAUGAAAACUCCAGAAACGCACAGGAACGAAAUACCUCCCAGAAACAUGAAGCAAUCAUCGAAGACUCACUGGUAAUAUUUUUAAAAAGUAUACAGAUCAAAGCAAAAAGAAGCCAUGUGUAACAAAGAGAAAUGUGCAAAUAUUUUUUAAGGCAGUAUUAAGUGCAAGAGGAGUAACAUGAAAUAAACAUUCUUUCACAUGGCUACUGGGAAUAUAAAUUUCGCUCCAGAAAGGCCGUAGCAGUUUGACGAUAGGUGGCAAAACCUUAAGAUUGUGUACUGGGGCCCAGAAUUUUUAUUUCUAGGAAUGUAUCCUGAGGAAAUUAUCCGAGAUCCCCACAAACUGCAAUGUUUAGGAAUUGUCCUUAUAGCAUUGCAUACACAAGAAAAACAGAGAAAAGCCUGAUCCCUGUCAGUGGAAAAGGGGUUCAAUGAAUUACGGUGUGUCUGCAUGAGGCUUUUAUGACAUUAAAAAUUGUUGAACAACGGCCAGGCACAGUGGCUCAUGCCUGUAAUCCUAACACUUUGGGAGGCCAAGGUGGGAAGAUUGCCUGAGCUCAGGAGUUUGAGACCAGCCUGGGCAACACGGUGAAACCCCGUCUCUACUAAAAUACAAAAAAUUAGCCGGGCGUCGCAGCAUGCGCCUGUAGUCCCAGCUGCUCAGGAGGCUGAGGCAGGAGAAUUGAUUGAACCCGGGAGGCAGAGGUUGCACUGAGCUGAGAUUAAGCCACCGCACUCCAGCCUGGGCGACAGAGCAAGAUUCCGUUCCCAAGAAAAAAAAAUUGUUCAACAAUAAGGGCAAAGGGAGAGAAUCAUAACAUCUGAUUAAACAGAAAAAGCAAGAUUUUUAAAACUAACUAUAUAAGGAUGGUCCCAGCUGUGUCAAAAGGAAGCUUGUUUGUAAUACGUGUGCAUAAAAAUUAAAUAGAGGUGAACACAAUUAUUUUAAGGCAGUUAAAUUAUCUCUGUAUUGUGAACUAAGACUUUCUAGAAUUUUACUUAUUCAUUCUGUACUUAAAUUUUUUCUAAUGAACACAUAUACUUUUGUAAUCAGAAAAUAUUAAAUGCAUGUAUUUUUCAAAAUCAAA